GCAGUCGCGCACCGACGCUCAAACGCGCGCUCCAACCCGCAGCCUCCUCCUGCCUCACCGCCCGAAGAUGGCGGCUCUCAAACUCCUCUCCUCCGGGCUUCGGCUCUGCGCCUCUGCCCGCGGAUCUGGGGCAACCUGGUACAAGGUAAAGUGCGGGGGAAGAGGAAGGCCAUGGGCAGGAAGAACGUGGACCAAACCCUGAGUGGUGCCCGCGUUUUCUUCUCUGCCCCUACCCGCUCUCUCCAGCCUGGGAUCUGGCAUCCGUGGCGCGGUGCCCUGGUCACGGACACGCGGCGACGCGUUCCUGGCCUCGCCGGCCCCUCGGAUGACCGCCUUUGCUUGGUUCUGCAGUCGCUUCCCUGAUGGAGCGAGACGCGAUAAAGAAGCGCGCGGAGAGGCUGAGAAGGGGCGGGAGGACUCCUGGCAGCGCUCCCGAGCCCUUUGGCGCUCGUCGGCUUCCCUCCUGGCACCCGCCCUUGGAUAGGGACUCUGAGGGUCUGAACGGGGGGAGGAGGGCGCCAGUAUAUGGAGGUUUAGGAGUGAGGCAACAGCGGGUAGGUUUGCGCCCCCGAUGUUGGAUCUCUGGGCAGAGGAACCUCUAGAGGCCCAGAACCUGAGGCUGGGUUAGCCAUGGCUCUGCUCGAGUUCACCGGGGCUGGAUGCCGGGUGCGGCGGGUGUGGAAUGCCGCUCCCAUCCUCUCCUCCCUAUUUGGCUCUGCUGCCCCGUAGACUGGAGCGCUCGCCAGGGCGUCUUGCCGGCCAAGCUGGGAAACCAUCCGAGGGAUGUGUUUGUUCCUUUUCCACCAGUGCUCAUCGCCAUACCAAGUUUUAUACAGAUCCAGUAGAAGCUGUAAAAGACAUCCCUGAUGGUGCCACGGUUUUGGUUGGUGGUUUUGGGCUAUGUGGAAUUCCAGAGAAUCUUAUAGAUGCUUUACUGAAAACUGGAGUAAAAGGACUAACUGCAGUCAGCAACAAUGCAGGGGUUGACAAUUUUGGUUUGGGGCUUUUGCUUCGGUCCAAGCAGAUAAAACGCAUGGUCUCUUCAUAUGUGGGAGAAAAUGCAGAAUUUGAACGACAGUACUUAUCUGGUGAAUUAGAAGUGGAGCUGACACCACAGGGCACACUUGCAGAGAGGAUCCGUGCAGGCGGGGCUGGAGUUCCUGCAUUUUACACCCCAACAGGGUAUGGGACCCUGGUACAAGAAGGAGGAUCGCCCAUCAAAUACAACAAAGAUGGCAGUGUUGCCAUUGCCAGUAAGCCAAGAGAGGUGAGGGAGUUCAAUGGUCAGCACUUUAUUUUGGAGGAAGCAAUUACAGGGGAUUUUGCUUUGGUGAAAGCCUGGAAGGCGGACCGAGCAGGAAACGUGAUUUUCAGGAAAAGUGCAAGGAAUUUCAACUUGCCAAUGUGCAAAGCUGCAGAAACCACAGUGGUAGAGGUUGAAGAAAUUGUGGAUAUUGGAGCAUUUGCUCCAGAAGACAUCCAUAUUCCUCAGAUUUAUGUACAUCGCCUUAUAAAGGGAGAAAAAUAUGAGAAAAGAAUUGAGCGUUUAUCAAUCCGGAAAGAGGGAGAUGGGGAAGCCAAAUCUGCUAAACCUGGAGAUGACGUAAGGGAACGAAUCAUCAAGAGGGCCGCUCUUGAGUUUGAGGAUGGCAUGUAUGCUAAUUUGGGCAUAGGAAUCCCUCUCCUGGCCAGCAAUUUUAUCAGCCCAAAUAUAACUGUUCAUCUUCAAAGUGAAAAUGGAGUUCUGGGUUUGGGUCCAUAUCCACGACAACAUGAAGCUGAUGCAGAUCUCAUCAAUGCAGGCAAGGAAACAGUUACUAUUCUUCCAGGAGCCUCUUUUUUCUCCAGCGAUGAAUCAUUUGCAAUGAUUAGAGGUGGACACGUCGAUCUGACAAUGCUAGGAGCGAUGCAGGUUUCCAAAUAUGGUGACCUGGCUAACUGGAUGAUACCUGGGAAGAUGGUGAAAGGAAUGGGAGGUGCUAUGGAUUUAGUGUCCAGUGCGAAAACCAAAGUGGUGGUCACCAUGGAGCAUUCUGCAAAGGGAAAUGCACAUAAAAUCAUGGAGAAAUGUACAUUACCAUUGACUGGAAAGCAAUGUGUCAACCGCAUUAUUACUGAAAAGGCUGUGUUUGAUGUGGACAAGAAGAAAGGGUUGACUCUGAUUGAGCUCUGGGAAGGCCUGACAGUGGAUGACGUACAGAAGAGUACUGGGUGUGAUUUUGCAGUUUCACCAAAACUCAUGCCAAUGCAGCAGAUCGCAAAUUGAAAUAUGGAUAUUUGUACCAGGCUGCGUGUUUUUCAUUUUAAACACACAAGAUUUAAUUGAAAGGACAUCAAUAAUCAUAAUUGUGUAUUUAACAGGUGGUUUUUUAUUAGUUUUCUUGUGUUUCAGACUUUAUGCAGCCAUAUAAACUGUUCUCUAGGCAUGCUGUGACAUUUUAAUAAAAAGCAAAAGGAGCAUUUAUAAUUAUCUCAUUUGUUAAGGCUGAGAAGGUUGUUUUUAUAAUAGGUAAUUAUAUUGAAUGCAUUUUCACUGAAUAUGGUAUGUAUGCUAAAUUAUAUGAACCUUUCCCCAAGAAGGGCCCUAGAAAUUGAUGUGGCUUUCCUCUUAAAUAUUAAUUAUUAGUCCUGAAAGAAAGAUAACAUAUGUGAUUUUUGUGGUUAGGAGAGUUGCUGUCAUGAUUGUUUUUUCUUCAGCCUCCUCUGACUUUUCUUUUGGGGCUUCAGAUUUUAUGAUUACAUCUUGUCCCCCUAGAACAUCCCCCUUCCUCCCAUACUGCUUUUAAACAGAUGCCCAAGAAGGCAAGCAGGAAUGCCUCUUGUGGGGGAGGGCAGGGAGAAAUAACUAGUUCAAACCAACUAUCUAUCUAUGCUUUGCAAAGACUAAGGCGUAUUAUAGGAAGAGGGCUAGAAACCUAACUGAUUCUUCUCAGUUUUCUCAUUUUAAAACAGCCCAGUAUUCCUUUGUAUCCUCAAGGGUCCUUGAGAAUACUUCUGUUAUUGAGACCCUGUGGGCUACUUGUACUGUACCUCCUCUCAAGCCAAGAAGGGCUGUGGGAUAAUUUACCAUGAAUCCUUAGUAGCAAUGACAGCAGAGUUAAAAAAUAAAAGGUGUUUUACUUUCAGGCUCUUGUUUUGGUUCAGAGGAGAUUUUAAAUAUUGAAUGACACUUCUACAGAACAACGGUUUUUCUUCUGCCAAGGCUACUUCCUUUAACGAAGUGCCUUUAAUUCAGCCUUAUCCAACUAGGGAAAAUAAUGUUGGACAAGUCUAGGAUUUGAAGAGUCAGUGAACUUUUAGUGUCAGGGAAUAAACAUGGUGGGUAGAUUAGGUUUGAAAAAAACUUCCUUAGAGGUAUUUAUUCUCAAUACCUGACAGGGGCCCAUGGGAAUGACUUCAGAAGCAUCCCGGAUAAUAGAUGGGUAAAAAGUCUAGGCACCCUGAAGAACAGGUGAGACAGCUGGCCUCUGGACAGAGGUAGGCAUAGUACAGUACGAUAUAUCAUUCCUCUGGUCCUAAAUAUACAAACUUAUUCAUGUUUUUAGGUGAUGAUGGUCAUUGAAACUCACUUCUUUUCAGGUGUAGCUACAAUUGUGUAAUGUACAAUAUUAGAGAAAGGACAGGCUUUUUAUGAGUAACACACACCAUAUAUAAAACAGCCUUUCUGGCUGACCACAUGGUUAAAUGCAUACCUUCCCAGUACUGGGGGGAAAAAAUGACCCUUCUUAGAAUGUGCAAGUUCCAUGAGAGUAAUAUAUUGAUAUGAUUUUGAAAAGAAUUGUUGAUAGUUACAUCUUCAAACUUAUCAUUCCAGUAUGCAUCUUUAAGAUAAUGUGAUUCUAAGUAGAUGACUUUAUAUUCUUGAUUGAAGAGUGCUAUACAUGUUAAGAAAUGCAUUAAGGAAUACAAUAAAUAUUCUAAAGUGAUGUA